GCCAGAAAGCUCAGUCUCCUGCUCAAAACAGGAGCGCAGCAGCCGGAGGGAGUGGGGACAAGCUCGCUGAACACUGGGCGUCUCGACAGGGACCAGAGCCUGCAGGACUGUUCCGAGACGCUGCGGUGGCGGCGGCGCCGGAGGACGCGGAGGACUCCCUGGCCACCCGCCCUCCGUGCGCUCUGCCACCGGGCGCUCAGCAGAGACCCCGGGCUGCGGCUGCACUUGCUGAGUGCCUCUCCCCGCCGCCGCAGCCCAGAGGCGCCCAGCACCUGGAGCUCACUGGAGCUGAGGGUCCGAGCUGAGCGGGCUGUUGUAAAGCCGAAAGGCGAGUCAGUGACUGGGACCUCUGUCCUGGUGGCGACGGAGAGAAACAGUGAGCCCGAGGGGCGCGGGCACAGAACUGUCCAGCUCCGAGAACUGGGGUCCGCCAGCCGGCGGGGAAAGCAGCUGAGCGCGGAGGCGAGUGAGCGGACGCGUCCCGGGGUCUUUGCAGUCCCCGCCGGCCCCAAGGCACCGACUCUCGGUCAGUUGGGCGCGGCAGGGCGGGAGGGGCGCGCCAUGGAGGCGCCGGGUCGCGCCAGUAUGCUCCAGGCCAAGUGAAGCGGUCCGGCUGGGGUCGGCGGGACCCGCGGGCCAUGUACGGCGACAUAUUCAACGCCACGGGCGGCCCCGAGGCGGCGGUAGGCAGCGCGCUGGCCCCAGGAGCCACGGUCAAGGCAGAAGGCGCUUUGCCGCUGGAGCUGGCCACUGCGCGCGGUAUGAGGGACGGCGCGGCCACAAAGCCCGACCUGCCCACCUACCUGCUGCUCUUCUUCCUGCUGCUGCUCUCGGUGGCGCUCGUCGUCCUCUUCAUCGGUUGCCAGCUGCGCCAUUCGGCCUUCGCCGCGCUGCCCCACGACCGCUCGCUGCGCGACGCCCGCGCGCCCUGGAAGACGCGGCCGGUGUAGCUUGGGACUGAGCCACGGCCGCCGGGCGCCCCGUCCCGACCUAGCCAAGAGCAGCCAGCUUGAGCCUGGUAGGGAGGGCACGACACCGGGGAUCGCUGGCCCCUGGGAACACGGUGCCCUGACCCAAAGACCCUUCCUGAACUAGAGUGGCAACCCGAGAGGAAAGGGAGACCGAGGCGUCGGGAGCCUGUGUAGGGUCUCGAUCCCAGUACCUGUAGGUACCGUGAUUCUGAUCCCCUGGCCAAAUCUUUCUUCCUCUGGACAGAGGGUCCAGUCGGGAAACCUUCCCGAAAGACGGCGGUCGGGUCGGGAAACCUUCCUGAAAGACGGCGCGCCAGCCCGUCUUGCUUGCUCGCCGCCUGCUGACUUCCUUACUUUGCACACGGAAGGGGCAGGAACCGCAAGCGUGCAACUAGCCUGGAGCUACCCGUCUGGACUCGCAGGCCCUGUGGCUGUUUCCCACAGCUGCUACGGCCUCUCUUGCUCCUUGACACCGAGGAGGACCCCACUAGGAUCCGAGCGUCGUGAACUCACCUGAACUUUGGAAGGUUGGCACUGGGGGGCCGCAUCCCCCUGGGAAAUGACUGAACGCGGGGUUUCAGUGGGUCCCGCCUGGGUCUAAGGACCCAGUUUCUUCUGUGAGCACGGGCAGUGGGAGGCCGGUGGAAAGGCGCAGGGGCCCACCUACGCGUCUCACAUCUUCAGGGGCGCAUUUCUACAAUAAAAACUCACCCAAUUAGACCUA